AAAAAAAUGCUUAAUAUUACUAAUCAUCAGAGAAAUGCAAAUUAAAACCACGACGAGAUACCAUCUCAUGUCAGUCAGGAUGGCUAUUAUUAAAAAGUCAAAAAACAGAUGUUGGCAAGGAUGUGGAGAAAAGGGAACACUUACACACUUGGUGGGAAUGUAAAUUAUUUCUGCACCUGUGGAAAGCAGUUUGGAGAUUUUUGCAAAGAUCUAAAAAUAGAAGUCCCAUUCGACCCAGCAAUCCCAUUACUGGGUAUCCUACCAAAGGAAAGUAGCUCAUUCUACCAAAAAGACACCUGCACUUGUAUGUUUAUUGCAGCACUAUUAACAACAGCAAAGACAUGGAAUCAGUCAAGGUGCCCAUCAAGAGUGGAUUGGAUUUUAAAAAUGUACCUAUACACCAUGGAAUACUAUGCAGCCAUAAAAGUGAAUCAAAUAAUGUCCUUUGCAGCAACAUGAAAGCAGCUGGAGGCCAUCAUCCUAAGCAAAUUAACACAGAAAUGGAAAACCAAAUACCACAUGUUCUGACUUACAAGUGGGAGCUAUACAUUGAGUGCACAUAGACACAAAGAUGGGAACAAUAAGCACUUAAGAUUCCAAAAGUGGGGAGGGAGGGGGGCAAGCGUUGAAAAACUUAUCAAGUACUAUGUUCCCUACUUCGGCAACAGCAUCAUUAGAAGUCCAAACCUCAGCAUCACACAAUAUACCCUUGUAUCAAACCCCCAUGUGUACCUCCUGAAUCUAAAAUUUAAAAAACAGGCAUCUGUUCAUGUCCUUUGCCCACUUUUAAUGUUAUUUGUUUUAUUCUUGUUCAUUUAUUUAAGAUCCUUAUAGAUUCUGGAUAUUAGUGCUUUGUUGGAUGCAUAAUGUGCAAAUAAUUUCUCCCAGUCUGCAGGUUGUCUGCUUAUUCUGUUGAUUGUUUCUUUCGCUGUGCAGACGCUGUAGUUCAAGUGAGUCUCAUUUGUCUAUUUUUUGUUUUUGUUGCAUUUGCCUUUGAGGUCUUAGUCAUAAGUUCUUCACCUAGGCCAAUGUCCAGAAGAGUUUUCCCUAGAUUUUCUUCUAGGAUCUUUAUAAUUUGAGGUCUUACAUUUGAGUCUUUGGCACAUCCUGAGGUAGUUUUUGUAUAUGGUGAGUAUUAGAGGCCCAAUUUCAUUCUUCUGCAUAUACCUAGUCAGUUUUUCCUGCACCACUUACUGAAUAGGGUAUCCUUUCCCCAGCAUUUAUUUUUGUUGACUUUGUCAAAGAUCAUUUUAAAAAAUGAUUUUUUUUGGUGGUUUUGAAUUGUAGAAGUUCUUUUAUAUAUUCUGGAUGUGAAUUCAGUAUUAGUUUUAUGAUUCACAAAGAUUUUCUCCUAUUCUGUGUGAGUUGUUUUUCAUUCUGUUGAUAGUGUCCAUUGAUGUACAAAAAACUUUAAUUUUUCUAACGUCCAAUUUAUUAUUUCUUCUAUUACCUGUGCUUUUGGUGUCAUCCAAGAAAUCACUGCCAAAUCCAAUGGCAUCAAGUGCUUCCCUUAUGUUUUCUUCUAAGUGUUUUCCAGUUUAAGCGCUUACAUUUAGUUCUUUGAUCCAUUUUGAGUUAAUUUUUGAAUAUACUGUAAAGUAAGAGUCCAGCUUGUUCUUUUGCAUGUGUAUAUCCGGUUUUCCCAACUCCAUUUGUUGAAAAGACUAUUUUUUCCAUUGAAUAGUCUUGGCACUUGUCAAAAACGAUUGACCUUGUAUUUGAGAGACUCUAUGGUAUUCCGUUGGUCCAUACGUCUGUCUGUAUACCAGUACUACACUGUUUUUGAUUACUGUAGUUUUGUGGUAAGUUUUGAAAUCAGGAUGUGUGAGAACUCCAAUUUUGUUAUGUUUCAAAUGAAUUUUAGGGGUUAUAGUUCUGUGCCAACCAUUUUUCUUUCAAGGCUUGAAAGUAGUUGUUUCAUAUAUUUGUUCUAGUGUUCUAGUUCUUAUGAUGUGAGGACGUAUUUGGUGCCAGUUACUCCACUGUGGCAGACAGUGGAAAUCUAGUAGUUUUCAAUUUUAUCAAACACAUUUUAUAUGUACUUUUUUGGGAGGAGCAUCUGUUGAGAUAACAGAUGAUACUUCUCUUUUCUUCUGAUAAGAUGAUGGAUUACACUGUUUUCAUUUUCAUCCAAAUGUUAACCGAUGUUGUAUUUCAGGAAUAAACCCCACUUUUUCAUGAUAUUAUUUUUUUAUGUACUAUUGAGUUUAAUUUGCUGAGAUUUGGUUUAGGAUUUUACACUUGAUUUAACACUUAAGAUUAGCCUGUAAUAUUCUCUUUCCUGUAAGUUCUUUUUUAUUUUGGUAACAAGGUUACGUCAGCAUCAUAUGAGUUGGGAAAUAUUCUCUUCCAUGAAAGAGUUUGCAUACCAAACAGUGCGGUUCCUGGAAGGGCUUCUAAGACCUUUAUGUGUUUGAAUGCUUGUUCUUGUACCUAGGCUUUCUUACCCUUUUCUUUGCCUUCCUUCUUCUUGCUUAUUCUUCACAGCCCAGCUCAGGGAACAUUUACUGUGGGAAACAUUUCCUGAGUUUUCUGGUCUCACUGGGUUGUGAAUCCCCCUUCUGUCUAUUGUGAAGGCAGCUUAAUCCUAGCUCUUUCCCUAGCGGGAAAACGUUAGCAAGUCAUUCUAUUUAUUUUUGUAAGUGUUUCAGUGGCAUGCUUAACACAGGGCACUGCUAAUACCUGCUACAAAGCCCAUUCUCCUUCCCCCUCAUGUCCCUCCUCAACCCUCUUUAUGUACCCUACGUAGUUCUGACCUCCUUCUGUUACCCUGCUCUCUGUGAAUUACUCCAUGCACAUGGCACAUGUCGGAUAUUGCCAUCUGCUUGUUAGUAUCCACUGUUGAUCUUGAGUUUCUGAGGGUCAGUUGUUUAUGGCUAUUGAGUACAUGAAUGAAUGAAUGAGUUUUCUUAUUUCUUCCUCCAGUGUGGUAGAAUCUAGCAAUGAAACUUGUAUUAUAUUUGGAUAGAAGAGUUUUAGUUGUAGAUUAAUUUUCUUUCCUAUUCAGAUUUUUUAAAAAAAAUUUUAUCAGCUUUUGUAAAUUAUAUCUUUCUAGUUAGUAAUUUGUCUAUUUAAAUUUAAAGUUAAGGCUAAAUUAAAGUUAAAGUUAAGGCUAAAGGUUGUUUGUAAUAGUGUGUGAUAUUUGAACGUCUGCAGAAGCUGUUAUGCCCCCUUCUAAAAUUUCUGACAGUUGCAUUGAUAGUUGUCUCUUUUUCCGAUCAGUGUUAGUAAAGUUUUACUUUUUUUCUUAUCUUCAAAGAACAAACCUACACUUCUGUUGAUAUCUUUGUUUUAUUAACUUCUGAUCUUUAUUAUUGCCUCAAUUCUACUUUCAUUUAUUUUAAUUUUUAUUCUUUUUAAACUUUUUGAGAUGGAUACAUAGCUUGUUGAUUUUGCCAGCUUGAUUUUCUUUUGCAGUUUUAGAAUUGAGUUAAACAUGCUAACUGCAUUCCGUAAGCUUUAGUCUGUUGUAUUUUCCUUAACAUGUAGUUUUAAAUAUUUUUGAAAAAUCUCACACAACACUAUUAAUUGACUCUACUUGGGUCUUCUGUCUAUCCAUAUUGUAUAUUCAAAUUUUUGUCUCCUUUUUAAGGCUCAUUUUGAAAUGCAACCUUUUCUGAGAAGCCUUUCCAGAAAACUUUCCCUCUUCUAAAGAUCUAUAGUUGUCUGGUAAUACCUUCCUUAUGACACUUAUUUUUACCUAGAAUUAUAGUUACUUAUGUAUAUCUCAGAUCUCACUUUGAACAGCAUGUCCCUUGAGAACAAACUCUCAACUGAAAAUUUUAAUAAUAUGCAUAUUUUUUAGUUUUACUGAGGUAUAAUUUUAAACAAAAUUUUACAACUUUAUAUGUCUUGUUUAGUUUGUAUAUGUGCAUAUACUAGGUGAUACCAUUACCACGAACAAGGUAUUAGACAUAUCUGUUGCCUCUAGAUUUUUUUGUGUGUUCUUUUGUGGGUAUGGGUGUGUUGUAAAGAAUAGUUAACGUGGGAUCUAUUCACUUAAUGUAUUUAAAAGCAGACACAGGGUUUCACCAUAUUGGCCAGGCUGGUCUCAAACUCCUGAAACCCCAUCUCUACUAAAAAUACAAAAAUUAGCUGGGUGUGGUGGUGUGCACCUGUAGUCCCAGCAACUAGGGAGGCUGAAGCAGAAGAAUCGCUUGAACCUGAGAGGUGGAGGUUUCAGUGAGCUGAGAUCACGUCACUGCAUUGCAACCUGAGUGACCGAGCAAGACUCUGCCUCAAAAAAUAUAUAUAUAUUUAUAUUUUAUAUAUAUAUACAUACAUAUAUUUUAAAGUACACAAUACAAUAUUGUUAACUGUAGGUACUAUGUUGUGCAGCAGAUCUCUAGAACUUAUUUAUCUCGUGUUACAGAAAAUUUAUACCAAUUGAAAAACAAUUUCAUGUUUCUUCCCCCUCUAUCCUCUGGCAACUGCCAUUCUACUCUCUGCUUCUGUGAGUCUAGUAUCUUUUUUUGGUGCUUCAUUAAAGUAGAUUCAUCUAGUAUUUGUGUGUGUUUGUGAUUGGCUUUUUUUACUUAGCAUAAUGCCCUCUAGGUUCAUCUAUGUUACUGCAAAUGGCAGGAUUUUCUUAUUUUUUAAGGUUGAAUGGUAUACCAUUAUAUAUAUAUGCUGCGUUUUAAAAAUUCACUUGUUUGAUUUGUUUUUCUAGUCUCUAUUUCAUUUAUUUCUGCCCUGAUCUUUGUUGUUUCUUCCUUUUGCUAACACCAGGCUUCGUUUUUCUCUAAUUCCUUGAGAUGUAACAUUAGCUUGUUUAUUUGAGAUCUUUCUUCUUUCUUUCUUUCUUUUUUUUUUUGAGACGGAGUCUCGCUCUGUCCCCCAGGCUGGAGUGCAGUGGUGCGAUCUCGGCUCACUGCAAGCUCUGCCUCCCGGGUUCACACCAUUCUCCUGCCUCAGCCUCCUGAGUAGCUGGGACUACACGCACCCGCCACCAUGCCCGGCUAAUUUUUUGUAUUUUUAGUAGAGACGGAGUUUCACCGUGUUAGCCAGGAUGGUCUCAAUCUCCUGACCUCAUGAUCUGCCCACCUCGGCCUCCCAAAGUGCUGGGAUUACAGAGCCACCAUGCCCGGCCUCUUCUUUCUUAAUGUAGCAUAUAUUGCUAUAAAAUUUCCCCUUUGUACUGCUUUUGCUGCCUGUUACAAAUUUUGGUAUGUCGUGUUUUCAUUUGUCUCAAGACAUUUAAAAUUUUUUUCUUUGACCAACUGGUAGUUCAGGAGUAUUAAUUUCCACGUUUGUGAAUGUUUUACCUUUCCUCUUAUUGAUUUCUAGUUUCAUAUAAUUGUUGAAAAAAUAUUUCAGUCUUCUUUAAUCUGUUAAAACUUGUUAUGUGGCCUAAGGUGAUCUUCUAAAGAAUGUUCUGUGUGUGCUUGAGAAGAACUGCUGUUGGCUAGACUGUUCUGUAUAUAAUCUGUUAGGUCUAUUUGAUUUAAUGUGUUGUUCAAGUCUGCUGUUUCUUUAUUGAUUUUCUGUCUGGAUGACCUUUCCACUGUUGAGAGUGGGCUACUGAAAUCUGUUAUUGUAUUGGUAUCUACUUUCCUCUUUGUUCUAUUAAUAUUUGCUUUAUAUCUUUAGGUGCCCUGAUGUUGGGUAUAUGCAAUUGUGUCUUCCUAAUGAGUUGACCUUUUUAUCAUUAUACAAUGAUCUUUUUUGUGUCUUGUGACAGUUUUUGAUGUAAAGUCCAUUUUGUCUGAUAUAAGAAUAGCCACCUCUGUGCUCUUUUAAUUACCAUUUUCAUGAAAUAUCUUUUCUAUCCCUUCACUUUCAGCUUAAAUGCACCCUUAUAGCUAAAGAGAGUCUCUUGUAGGCAGCAUCUGGUUGGAUCUUGUUUUUGUAGUCACUCAGCCACUCUGUCUUUUUUUAAAAAAUUAUAAAUUCAGGUGGUGCUUGUUAUGUUGGUGUAUUGGGUAAUCCUAGGGUUUGGGCUUCUAAUGAACCCAUCACCCAAAUAAUAAACGUAGUACCCAAUAGGUAGUUUUUCCAACUCUUUCCCAUCUUCGUCCCCCACCCUUGGAAUCCCUAGUAUCUAAUAUUUCUAUCUUUAUGUCUCCUGUGUAUCCAUUGUUUAGCCAAUUGAUAAGUGAGAGCAUGCAGUAUUUGAUUUUCUGUUUCUGCAUUAAUUCUCUUAGGGUAAUGGCCUCCAGCUGCAUUCAUGUUGCUCCAAAGGACACAAUCUCAUUUUUUAUGGCUGUGUAGUAUUCCAUGGUAUAUAUGUACCACAUUUUCUUUAUGCAAUCCACCUUUGACAGAAACUUAGGCUGAUUGCAUGAUUUUGCUAUUGUGAAUAGUGCAGUGAUAAACAUACAAGUGCACAUGACCUUUUGAUAAAAUGAUUUCAUUUCCUUUAAGUAUAUACCCAGUAGUGGGAUUGCUGGGUCAAAUGGUAGUUCUAUUUUAGUUCUUUGAGAAUUCUCCAUACUAUUUUUCUACAGGGGUUGAACUAAUUCACAUUCUCUACCAACAAUUUAUAAGCAUUCUCUUCUCUACAGCCAUACCAACAUCUAUUUUUUUUUUACUUUUUAGUAAUAGCCAUAUUACCAGUGUGAGAUGAUAUCUCAUUGUGGUUUUAAUUUGUAUUUUUAUCUGAUGAUUAGUGAUGUUGAGCAUUUUUUCAUGUUUUUUGGCUGCUUGUAUGUCCUUUGAGAAAUCUGUUUAUGUCCUUUGCCUACUUUUCAAUGGUGGUUUUUUUUCUUGUUGAUUUAUGUUCCUUAUAGAUCAUAGAUAUUAGUCUUUGUUAGAUGUGUAGUUUGCAAAUAUAUUCACCCAUCUGUAGGCUGGCUGUUUACUGUGUUGAAACUGUUUCUUUUGCUAUGCUAAAGCUCUUCAGUUGAAUUAAGUCUGAUUUGUCUAUUUUUGUUUUUGUUGCAUUUGUUUUUGAGGUCUUAGUCAUAAAUUCUUUGCUUGGGCCAAUCCAGAAGAGUUUUCCCUAGGUUUUCUUCUAGGAUUUUUAUAGUUUGAGGUCUUACAGUUGAGUCUUUAAUCUGAUUUGAGUUAAUUUUUGUAUAUGGUGAGAGGUAGAAGUCCAGUUUAAUUCUUCUUUAUAUAGCUAGCCAGUUUUCCCCAGCACCAUUUAUUGAAUAGGGAGUCCUUUCACCAUUGAUUGGUUUUGCCAACCUUGUCAAAGAUCAGAUGGUUGUAGAGGUGUGGCUUUAUUUCUGGGUUCUCUAUUCUAUUCCAUUCAUCUAUGCAUCUGUUUUUGUAGUGUAGCAGUAAAAUUUGAAUUUGGGUAAUGUGAUGUCUCCAGCUUUAUUUUUGUUUGGGAUUUCUUUGGUUAAUCAGGCUCUUUUUUGGUGCCAUGUGAAGUUUCCGUAAUUUUUUUGUAGUGCUGUGAAAAAUGACAUUGGUAAUUUCAUAGGAAUUGUGUUGAAUCUGUAGAUAUCUUUUGGCAGUUUGGUCAUUUUAGUUAUAUUGAUUCUUCUAAUCCAUGAGCAUGGAAUGUUUUUCCGUUUGUUUGUAUCAUCUAUAAUUUCUUUCAAAAGUGUUUUGUAGUUCUCCUUGUAGAGGUCUUUCGCCUUCUUGGUUAAACAUAUUCCUACUUAUUUUUUGUGUGUGGCUAUUUCUAGAUGGAAUUGAGUUCUUGAUUUGGUUCUCAGCUUGAAUGUUAUUGCUGCACAUUCUACUGAUUUUUGUACAUUGAUUUUUGUAUCUUGAAACUACUGAAUUUGUUUAUCAGGUCUAGGAGUCUUUUGGAUGAAUCUUUAACGUUUUCUAGGUACAGGACUAUGUCAACAGUGAACAGAGAUAAUUUGACUCCCUCUUUUCCUAUUUUGAUGUCUAUUGUUUCUUUCUCUUGUCUGAUUGCUCCAGCUAGGACUUUCAGUACUAUGUUGUAUAGGCAUGGGGAGAAUGGAUGUAUUAGUCAAUUCUGAUGCUGCUUAUAAAGACAUACUUGAGACUGGGUAAUUUAUAAAGGAAAGAGGCUUAAUUGACUCACAGUUCAGCAUGGAUAGGGAGGCCUCAGGAAACUUACAAUCAUGGCAUAAGGGAAAGCAGACACAUUCUUCUUCACAUGAUGGCAGGAAGGAGAAGUGCAGAGAGAAGGUGGCGGGGGAAGCCCCUUAUAAAACCAUCAGAUCCUGUGAGAACUGAUUCACUAUCCCAAGAACAGAAUGGAGGUAACCACCCCCAUGAUUCAAUUACCUCCUACCGGGUCCUUCCCACACCACAUGGGGAUUGUGGGAACUACAGCUCAAGUUGAGAGUUGGGUGGGGACACAGCCAAAGCAUAUCAGUGGACAUCCUUGUCUUGUUAUCAUUCUUAAGGGGAAUUCAUUCAAAUUUGCCCAUUCAGUAUGAUGUUAGCUGUGGGUUUGUCAUAAAUGGCUUUUAUUAUUUUGAGGUAUGUUCCUUCGAUGUCCAGUUUGUUGAAGGUUUUUAUGAAGGGAUGCUGGAUGCUAUUGAAUGCUUUUUCUGUGUCUGUUGAGAUGAUCAUACAGGUUUUGUUUUUAAUUCUGUUUGUGUGGUGAAUAAUAUUGAUUUGUGUAUAUUGAAUGAUCCUUGUUUCCCAGAAAUAAAGCCCACUUGAUCAUGAUGAAUUAUCUGGUUGAUAUGAUGUUGAAUUAAGUUUGCUAGUAUGUUGUUGAAGAUUUUUGCAUCUAUGUUCAGAAAGUAUAUUGACCAGUAGUUUUUUUUUUCUGUGUCCUUGCUAGAUUUUGAUACCAGGGUGAUGCUAGUUUUGUAGAAUGAAUCAGAGAGGAAUUGUCCUUGAUUUCCUAUAACAGUUUCAGUAAGAUUGGUGCCAGCUUUUUGAACAUUUGGUAGAAUGUGGCUGUGACUCUGUCUUGCCCAGGGCUUUUUUUGGUUGGUAGAUUUUUUAUUACCGAUUUAAUUAUCUAACUCAUUCGUCUGUUCAAGAUUUCAAUAUCUUUCUGGCUCAAUCUUUGGAGGUUGUGUUUUUCCAGGAAUAUAUCCAUUUCUCCUAGGUUUCCUAGUUUGUGUGCAUAGAGAUGUUCCUAGUAGUCUCUGGUGAUCUUUUUUCUUUCUGUGGUAUCAGUUGUAAUGUCACCUUUAUCAUUUUUUAUUGUGGUUAUUUGAAUGUUCGUUUUUUUCUUGAGUAAUCUUGCUAGCACUCUAUCAAUUUUGUUUCGAUGAACCAGCUUUUCAUUUUGUUGAUGCUUUGUUGUUGUUGUUUUGGUCUCAGUUUCAUUUAGUUCUCUAAUAUUUCUUUCUUUUUUUUCUGAUACCUUUGGAUUUGGUUUGUUUUCCUAAGUCCUUUAGAUAUGACCUUAGGUUGUUAAUUUGAGAUCUAUCUUUUCACGUAGGCAUUUAGCAGUAUAAACUUUCCUUUAAACACUGCUUUUGCUUUACUCAAGAGGUGUGGGUGUAUUGUCCAAGAAGAUACUUGAUAUGAUUUCAGUUUUUUUGCAUUUAUUGAGACUUGCUUUAUGACCGAGCUUGUGGUCAAAUUUAGAGAAUGUUGCAUGUACAGAUGAUUAAAGAAGUGGGUAUUUGCGGUUCUUGGGUGGAAUAUUCUGUAGAUGUCUAUUAGGUACUUUUGGUCAAGAGUCCAGUUUAAGUCCAGAGUGUUUUUUUUUUUUUUUUUUUUUUUUUUUUUGUUAGUUUUCUGCCUCAGUGAUCUGUCUAAUGCUGUCAGUGGGGUAGUGAAGUCCCCCACUAUUAUUGUUUCACUGUGUAUCUCUGAAGUCUACUAGUAUUUGUUUUAUAAAUAUGGGUACUUUGACAUUGGGUGCAGGUAUAGUUAGGAUAGUUAAGUCUUCUUGAUUGAAUUGAAUGUUUUAUCAUUAAAUAAUGCCAUCUUUUUCAUUUUCUUUUUUUAGCUUUGUUCAUUUAAAGUCUGUUUUAUGUGCUACAAGAAUAGCAACUCAUCCUCUUUUUUGUUUGUUUGUUUUUCAUUUGCAUGAUAGAUGUUUUUCCAUUUCUUUACUUUUAGUGUGGGAAUGCCGUUCCCUGUGAGGUAGAUCUAUUGAAGGCAGCAGAAUACUGUUUUUUAAAUCCAAUUUGCCACUCUGUGUCUUUUGAGUAGGGUAUUUAGACCAUUUACAUGUAAGACUAAUAUCGAUAUGUGAGGUUUCAUUUCUGUCAUAGCUUUCUUAGCUAGUUGUUUUGUAGUCUCAAUUGUGUAAUUGUUUUGUAGCAUCUGAGAACUUUGUACUUAUGUGUUGUUUUAUGGUAGCAGUAUCAUUCUUUCGUUUCCAUCUUUAGAACUUCUGUGAAUAUUUCUUGUAGGGCUUAUCUGGUGGAGACAAAUUCCCUUAACAGUUGCUUCUCUAAUAAAGGCUUUAUUUCUCCCUUAUUUAUGAAGCUGUUUGGCAGGAUAUGAACUUUUUGGCUGCCAUUUUUUUUUCUUUAAGAAGGCAAAAAUAGGCUUCAGUCUCUUCUGGCUUGUAAGGUUUCUGCUGAGAAGUCUGCUGUUAGUCUGAUGGGACUUCCUUUAUAGGUAAUUUGGGCCUUUUCUCUAGCUACCUUUAAGGUUUUUUUUUGUAUUAACCUUGGGAACGGUUGUGUUGUAUAGUAUCUCUCAGGUGUACUCUCAGUUUCUUAUAUCUGGUUCUUGACCUCUCUAGCAAGAUUAGGGAAAUUUUCCUGAAUUAUUUCCUCAAAUAUGUUUUCCAAUUUGCUUGCUUUUUCUUUGUAUUUCCAAAGGCUUUGUUCUUUUUUUUGCUUUAUCUGGGUUAAUUUGAAGGACCAGCCUUCAAGUUCUGAAAUUCUUUCUUCUGCUUUGUGUAAUCUGUUAUUAAAACUUCCAGCUGUAUUUUGAAAUUCCUUUAGCAAAAUUUUCAAUUUCAGAAGUUCUAUUUGUUUUUUUCUUAAUACAGCUAUCUUGUCUUUCAUACCCUGAAUUAUUUUUCUAGUGUCUUUGUAUUGGAUUUCAACUUUCUCUUGGAUCUUACUGAGUUUCCUUGAUAUCCUUAUUUUGAAUAUUUUAUCAUUUCAAAUUUUUCAGUUUGGUUAGUAUCCAUUACUAGAGAGUUGGUGCAAUCCUUUGGAGGUGUCAGGACAUCCUGGCUUUUUAUACUGCCAGAGUUCUUGCUGAUUCCUUCUCGUCUGAGGAGCUGCUACUUCUCAUUUUUGAGUUUGCUAUCAUUUGCAUGGGAUCUUUUAAUUUUUCAAUCCUUUUUCCCUUUAGGGUAUGACUGUGGUGUAUGUUGUGUAUGAUCUUUUUGUUUCAUUUAUUGGUACUUUCAGUGGGCCAAGGCUGUAUAUGGGUACGUUGGUUGUGGAUAGCCUCUGUGUAGUGACUUUCUUAGAUGCUGAUUGUUGUAGCGAUGUAUUGAACAUAUGAGCGGACACACUAUUUCCUGUGGGAUUGAGAGUGCAGGUGCAUAGGUCUUAGGAAACUUAUCUCAGACUAGCACUAAGCCCUUCUGGUAGCAGGUUUUUUGUUUGGUGGUGCAGUUCAGGCUGUAGUCCAGUAGAUGGAGAUGACACUUAAGAGUAGGAGACAGCUCAUGCCCAGGCUGAUGUCAAGUGGUAGCACCUGUGUUGACAGGAGGCAUGAGAGGGGUUAGGGGGCCAGUGGGAACAGGAAGCAAUCUUGUUGGGGCCCGCUGAGAUCUUGGAGGAAAGGUUGGGGAGGUGCACCAGGUCCUUAUCCUGAGUCAGCAGGAAUGCCAUCUGCUUCCCUAUCUUGCCCCUGUUGCAAAGCUCACGACCUUAGUUCAUAAAUACUUUUGGUUCCUGGUUGCAGAGCAGCUGUGGGCCACCGAAACACCCUCUUGAAGGCUUGGACAGAGUAUCUUACCCCAGUUCAGGGCAGGCAACUCUGUGAUUUCUCUGUUCUCUGUUGCUGGGAUGCUGCCAUUCUGUGUAGGGAGGGCGAGUUAGGCCCCGCCAUUCGAGUAAACCCCAUGCAGCAUGGGCUUACUUUGAGUAGGGAUGGAGCUGCUGUGAAAAGCUUAAAAAAUGCUUUCUCCGAAUGCAUUCCCCAGCCCCCAGUGGGAAGAACCUCUGCUGUGUCUGCAAUAGUGUAUGGCAUUGGAUGGGUGGGAGAUGUCCCUCUCUCCAUGUUCAUUUCCUGGUGUUGGCACUGCCUCCUUCAGCAAUCAGUGCUGCAUCCACAUUCCCUUUGUCCUAAGGGGACUUUGGUAGGCUGCACUCCCUUGUUGGUAGCCCAUGCUGGUGGUUAGAUCUCCAGGGGCCUCACAACUUCCUGGGGGCCCAUCAGUCUCCUGUGCUUGCCAAAGCCAGAGUGGGUUGUAAGUUAUAUUUGUGAGGGUUCUGGUGGUGUGAUGACUCAAGGGCGGAGAAACCCUAGGCAGGGCAGAGGUCCACUAGGUAUCUACACCAGUAUUGCACCUGUCAUCUCAGUUUGGGUCAGGGGAGUACAUGAAUUCCUACAGGAGCUAGCCAGCUGGUUCUCUAUCCCUGGGAAAUUCCCAAGUCACCACCGAUAGCUUUGCCCUAGGUCAUGAGGACAGAGGGGUUCCCAACAGUUUGGUGGUCAGCAGAUUGUCAGAGGGGUGAAGGGAGCAGAGCAGCAUUCCCACCUUUUUUUUUUGAACGGAGUAUCGCUCUUGUUGCCCAGGCUGGAUUGCAAUGGCAUGAUCUUGGCUCACUGCAACCUCCGCCUCCUGGGUUCGAGCAAUUCUCCUGCCUCAGCCUCUUGAGUAGCUGGGAUUAUAGGCACCUGCCACAAUGCCUGGCUAAUUGUUUUGUAUUUUUAAUAGAGAUGAGGUUUCACCAUGUUGGCCAGGCUGGUCUUGAACUCUUGUCCUCAAGUGAUCUGCCUGCCUCGGCCUCCCAAAAUGCUGUGAUUACAAGUGUGAGCCACCGCGCCCGGCCUCCCGCCUACUUUUUCUGCAGGAUUCCAGGUUUCUCUGGGGUUGAUCUCUGCCAGAUUCUUCCUCUUUGUCUUUUGUUUGGGGAAUUUAAUUGAUUUACAUAUAAAGUAAUUAUUGAUGGGUAAGGGCUUACUAUUGCUAUUUCAUUAAUUUUUUUCUGUCUAUUCUGUAGUUCUUUUCUUUCUUUCUUCUCCUCCCCUUUUGUCUUCUUUGGUGACUUGAUUUUUGUAGUGUUGUGCUUUGAUUUUUUUCUCUUUCUCUUUUGUGUAUCUCCUGUAAGUUUUUUCCUUUCUGGUUACCAUGGGACUUACAUAAACAUAUUUCUAACAGUCUAUUUUAAGCUGAUAACAGCUUAACUAUGCUCACAUACAAAACUACCCAUUUAUUCUCCCUUAAUUAUUUGUUAUUGAUGUCACAAUUUACAUCUUAAAUUGUGUAUCCAUUAAUUGUUAUAGUUCUUAGUACUUUUGUCUUUUAACAUUUAUAUUAGGGUUAAAAGUGACUUACAUACUUUACAAUAUUAGAAGAUUCUAUAUUUACUUAUAUAUUUACCCUAACCAGUGAGUUUUAUACUCCUGUGGUCUUUCAUGUUGCUAUUUAGUGUCUUUUUGUUUCAACUUGAGCAACUUCAUGUAGCGUUUUUCAUAAGGUAAACAUAGUGGUGAUGAACUUCCUCAGCUUUUGUUUGGGAAAUUUUUUCUUGCCUUCAUUUCUGAAGGACAGCUUUGCUGGGUAUAGCACUCUUGGUUAGUAGUUUUUUUUUUUUCUUUCAGCACUUUAAAUAUGUAGUGAUCCCCCGGUACCUGUGGGGUUAUCCAGGAAACUCCACAGAUAAUACAAUCCACAAAUUCUAAAGUCUGUUGUAUAAAAUAAUGUAUUUGCAUAUAGACCAUGUACAUCUUCCUGUAUACUUUACAUCAGCUGUAGAUUACUCAUUAUACCCAAUAAAAUGUAAAUGCAACAUAAAUAUUUGUUCUAACUAUAUUACACUUUUUAUUUAAAUUUUUAAUUGUUAGAUUGUUUUUUGUUUUGCUAUACAGUUGCUUGAAUCUCCAGAUGCAGAACAUGUCGAUAUGAAGGGCUGACUGUAUAUAUCAUCUCACUCUCUUGGCCUGCAUAGUUUCUGAUGAGGAAUCUGCCAGUAGUCUUAUGGAGCUCCUUUGCCUGUAAUGAGUCACUUUUCUCUUGCUGGUUUGAAAAUUCUGUAGUUGUCUUUGAUUUUUGACAUUUUGACUAUAAUGUCUUGUUCUAGACCUUUUUGGAUUUAUUCUGUUUGGGCUUCAUGAAUCUGGAUGUUCAUUUCCAUGCCCAGAUUUGGGAAUUAUUGAGUCAUUUUUUUAAUUAGGGUUUUUACCGCUUUCUCUUUCUCUUCUCCUCUGGGCCUUCCAUAAUGUAUAUAUUGGUUUGAUGGAGUACCAUGAUUUCCUUAAGAUUUCUUCACUUCUUUUCAUUAUUUUUUCAUUUUGCUGUUCUGGCUGUAAUUUCAAAUUGCCCAUCCUCGAGUUUUCAAAUUCUGUCUUCUGCUUGAUAAAAGUUUGCUGUUGAACCUCUCUUGCGAUUUUUUAAAUCCAGUUAUUCUUUAAUAAAAUCCAAUUUUCUAGUAUUUUAAAAAUUUAAUUAUAUUUAUUUUAUUUUAUGUUAUUUUUAAGAUGAGGUCUUGCUGUGUUUGUUGCCCAGAGCUGGAGUGCAGUGGUGUGAGCAUAGCUCACUGCAGAUUCAAACUCCGGGGCUCAAGCAAUCCUCCUGCCUCAGUCUUCUGAGUAGCUGGGACUACAGGCAUACACUACCAUGCCUGUCUAUCAAAAAAAAAUUUUUUUAUACAAGGGGUCUUGCUGUGUCACCCAGGCUGGUCUUAAAAUCCUGGCUUCAAGCAGUCUUCCCACUUCAGCCUCUUGAGUAGCUGGGAUUACAGGUGUGAGCCACUGUGCCUGGCUAAAAAAAAAAAAAAAAAAAAAAAAAAAAUUGCGUCUAUCUCUUUGUUGAUAUUCUCAGUUUGUCCAUGUUUUAUUUUUUGAUUUAAUUUAAUUGUCUAUCAACAUUCUCUUUUAUCUCACUGAGCUUCUUUAGGAUGAUUAAUCUGAAUUAUUUUCAGUAUUUGAAAAUUCCCAUUUUCACUUCAUAAAUUCCCAUUUAUUUUGGGUGAGUUGGUAGAGAUCUAUUUUCUUGCCUUUUUUCAAUGUUUUCUUGAUUCUUCAUGUUUCUUAUAUGAUUGUAUUCAUGUCUGCACAUUUGAUGAAACAACACUUUUUCCCUGUGUUGCAGAACAGUAUAAACUAUAGAGAGGCACCCUCCCUUCGUCUCUUGUUCCUGGCUGGUCCAGUCAUUUAACUGUCCCAGGCAUCUAGAUUCUACUGUUUUUAAUGCUAAGUAUGAGACAAGAUAGAAAUCAGGCCCUUGGAAAUGCACUGAAAGUUUGGGGACAAAGCUCAGUUUGUUUUUCCCACUCACUCCUGAAGAGAAAGCCUUAGUUCUCUGACUUUUACCAAUCUUGCUCAGCAGCGCUGGUGUAAGAGUUACCUGCCCCCUCUGUUUUGCUCCUAGUUGUCUCAGGCUCACAGGCUCUACCAGUCUUUCAGUGCUUCAAAUGUGAGAUGACAGAAAUUAGCCCUUGGGGAGUACACUGAAAUGGCAGUAGGCCAGGCAGCUGGCACACUCUUCACUGUCUCCUUCCCACUCAUGGGAGAAGUCAUGGGCUGAGGUGAUCCUCUGGCUCUGAACUAAGCCAGUUUGGGGGAGGGACUGAUGUGGGAAAAUUAAGUUUGCUCUUUGUAUUAGGCCCUUCUUUCAUUGCUAUAAAGAAAUACCUGAAAUUAGGUAAUUGAUAAAGAAAGUAGAUUAAUUGGCUUAUGGUACUGCAGGCUGUACUAGAAGCUGCUGGCAUCUGCUUGGCUUCUAGGGAGGCUUCAGGGAGUUUUACUAAUGGCGAAGGUAAAGUGGGAGCUUGCAUGUCACAUGGCAAAAGCAGGAGCAAGAAAUAGAGUGGAGGGGGGCAGGUGCCACACUUUACAGCAGCCAGGUCUUGGGAGAAUACACUCACUAUUACAAGGAUACCACAGAGCCAUAAGACAUCCAAUCCUGUGACUCAAACACCUCCUAACAGGUUCCACCUCCAACGCUGGGGAUUACAUUUCAACAUGAGUUGCAGGCGGGGACAAAUGUCCAAACUGUAUCACUCUUCUUCCUAUGUUGGUUGCAAGUUUUCUCAGCUUUGUUCUUGCGUAGAACAACACAGUUUUUUAACUGGAUUAAAAGUUUCUCACACAGGUAUUUCAGUCCAAAUAUUAUUUUUGUGUUUCUGAGGGUAAACCAACACCAGAGUUCCUGCUCUGCCAUCUUGAUGUCAUCUCUACACAUCUACUUUUUUUCCCCUAGAAUGUCUCUCUCCCCUGCUUGCAAUAUAGCAAACCUUUUCCUUUGGGGAAUUGUUCAUUUCUGUGUACUCCAGUCGUGAGGUUGUAAUGAGGGCUGCUAAUUACCUGUCACUCUCCUUCUGGCUUCAGGGAAGGGUGUGUGACUUAGACCUGGCCAAAUGGGUCAUCUCAUUUGGUCCAGUUAUGGUCAUGUGACUCAAGCAGUGACAAUGUGUUCAUUUCUGGAUUUCUAAAUGGCAAUUGUGAGAAUUCUUCUCAGAUUGCUAAGGAAUAUGAAUCCAAAGCUGAUUGAAAGUUGUCAAGUUUCGUUAAUGAAUAUCCUACUGUAGGGAGUAUGGUUGGCAGACAUUGAAAUAGAUGUAAUUUAGAGAAAUGACAAGCUACCAACAUUGAGAAUUCUUACUCAGAAACAUAUAUUUCUCCAUUUAUUCAGAAGUUUUAUUAGUUUGUUCUCACACUGCUAUAAAGAACUACCUGAGACUGGGUAAUUUAUAAAGAAAGGAGGUUUAAUUGACUCACAGUUCCACAGGCUUAACAGGAAGCAUGACUAGGAGGCCUCAGGAAACUUACAAUCAUGGCAGAAGGCGAAGGGGAAGCAAGCACUUUCUUCACUUGGUGGCAGGAGAGAGAGAAAAAAGGGGGAAGUGCUACACACUGUUAAACCAUUGAUCUUGUGAGAACUCACUCACUAUCAUGAGAACAGCAAGGGAGGAAUCUGCCCUAUGAUCCAGUCACCUCCAACCAAGCCCCUCCUCCAACAUGAGAUUUGGAUGGGGACACAAAUCCAAACCAUAUUAUUUCACCCCUGGCCUCUCCCAAAUCUCAUGUCAUUCUCACAUUGCAAAAAUACAAUUAUUCCUUCUCAACAGUCUCCCAGCUUUAACUCAUUUCAGCAUUAACUCAAAAGUCCACAAUCCAAAGUCUCAUCUGAGACAAGGUAAAUUCUUUCCAUUUAUGAGCCUGUAAAAUUAGAAACAAGUUACUUCCAAGAUACAAUGGAGAUACAUGCUCCCAUUCAAAAUGGGAGAAAUUGGCCAACACAAAGGGGCUAUAGGCCGCAUGCACUUCUGAAACCCAAUAGGGCAGUCAUUAAAUCUUAAAGCUCCAAAAUAAUCUCUUUUGACAUGAUGUCUCACAUUCAGGGCAUGCUGAUGCAAGGGAUGGGCUCCCAAGGCCUUGGGCAGCUCUGCCCCAUGGCUCUGCAGGGUACAGCCCUCCUCCCAGCUGCUUUUGUGGGCUGGCAUUGGGCGCCUCUGUCUUCUCCAUGUGCUCGGUUCAAGCUGUCCAUGGAUCUGCCAUUCUGGGGUCUGGAGGAUGGUGGCCCUCUUCUCACAGUUCCACUAGGCAGUGCCCCAGUGGGGACUCUAUGUGGGGACUCCAAUCCCACAUUUCCCCUCUGCAUUGCCCUAGUAGAGAUUCUCCAUGAGGGCUCUGCCCCUGCUGCAGACUUCUGCCUGGACAUCCAGGCAUUUCCAUACAUCCUCUGAUACCUAGGCAGAGGUUUUCAAACCUCAACUCUUGCCUUCUGCAUCCUGCAGGCCCAACACCAUGUGGAAGCUGCCAAGGCUUGGGGCUUGCACUCUCUGAAGCCAUGACCCGAGCUGUACUUUGGCCCCUUUUAGCCAUGGCUGGAGCUGGAAUGGCUGGGAUGCAGCCAUUCCCACGUCCCAAGGCUGCACAGAGCAGUUGGGCCCUGGGCCUUGCCCAGAAAACCAUUCUUCUCUCCUAGGCCUCCAGACCUGUGAUGAGAGUGACUGCCAGGGAGGUCUCUGAAAUACCCUGCAGACAUUUUCCCCAUUGUCUUGGCUAUUAACAGUCAGCUCCUCUUUACUUAUGCAAAUUUCUGCAGCAGGCUUGAAUUUCUCCCCAGGAAAUGUUUUUCUUUUCUACUGUAUGGUCAGACUACAAAUUUUCUAAACUUUUAUGGUCUGCUUCUCUUUUAAAUACAAGUUCCAAUUUCACACCAUCUCUUUCUUCAUGAAUAUGUGCAUACACUUUUAGAAACAGCCAGGUCAAAUCUUGAAUGCAUUGCUGCUUAGAAAUUUAUUCCACCAGAUACCCCAAAUCAUCUCUCUCAAGUCCAAAGUUACAUAGAUUUCUAGGGCAGGGGCAAAAUGCCACCAGUGUCUUUGCUAAAGCAUAGCAAGAGUGACCUUUACUCCAGUUCCCAAUAAAUUCCUCAUCUCCAUCUGAGACCACCUCAGCCUGGACUUCAUAGUUCAUAUCACUAUAGGCAUUUUGGUAAAAGCCAUUCAAUAAGUUUCUAGGAAGUUCCAAACUUUCCCAUAUCUUCCUGUCUUCUUCUGAGCCCUCCAAACUGUUCCAACCUCUGAAUGUUACCUAGUUCCAAAGUCACUUCCACAUUCUUAGGUAUCUUUAUAGCAGAGCCCCACUCCUGGUACCAGUUUUCUGUAUUAGUCCAUUCUCACACUGCUAUAAAGAACUUCCUGAGGCUGGGUAAUUUAUAAAGAAAGGAGGUUUAAUUGACUCACAGUUCUGAAGGCUUAACAAGAAGCAUGACUGGGAGGCCUCAGGAAACUUACAAUCAUGGUGGAAGGUGAAGGGGAAGCAAGCACUUUCUUUACAUGGUGGCAAGAGAGAGAGAGUGAAGGGGGAAGUGCUACACACACUCUUAAACCAUCAGAUCUCAUGAGAAUCAUUAUCAUGAGAACAGCAAGAGGGAAAUCCACCCCAUGAUCCAAUCAUCUCCCACCAGGCCUUUCCUCCAAUUCAACAUGAGAUUUGGGUGGGGACACAAAUCUAAACCAUAUGUUUUCUGAUUUUUGAAAAAAUUUUAUAAUUUUUUUCUAUGAGUCUGUCACAUUUCUUUUCAGGUUUGCUCAUAGGUGUUUUAUAAUUUUAGUUGAUAUUGUGAAUAAGAUCUCCCUCCCUACCCCCAUUACAUUUGCUAAGUGGUUUUUGAUAUGUUACUGGAAAGCUGCUGGUUUUGGAGUGUUUAUUAGCAUCUUUAUUCAGCCAUGUGCCUGGACCAUUAUAAAAUCUUUUUUGAUUGAGCCUUUUUUGUAUUCUAGGUAGACUAUCAGAAAGUUCAUAAAUAGUGAUAGUUUCAUGUUUUUAUUUCUAUUUCCUUUCUGUUUUAGUAAUACAUUUAAGAUUGCCAUUAAAAUAUUGACAAACAGUUAUUCCAGGCAACAUCUUUACCUCAUUCAUGAAUGUCUUUUAAUACUCCAGAUUAUUUUCUAUGAAUAUUUUUUAUUCACAGCUUUUAAUAAAUUUUAUAUUGGAUGAGUAUUGAGUUGGAUGAAAACAUAUUUUGAGAAUGCUUUAGAUUUUCCUACAUUUUCUCCCCUUUAUUCUUAAUGUAGUGAAUUAGGUUAAUGGAUGACACAAUAACAUAAUAAUUAUUAUUAACACAAGAGCAAUAAAAGAAUAACCUCCCUAUCUUGGUCAUAGCCUAGUUAUUUAAAUACAUUCCUUUAUUCAAAUGGAUUUACUUCAUGGAUCAUCCAUCCCUUGCUUGCUUCUUUCCUUUCUUCAUCUUUACCUCUCUCCUGCUUUCCUUCCCUCCAUCUACACAGGUCAAAGGAGCAGCAAGAAUAAAGACCCUGAGAUGGGUGUAUGCUUUGGUCUGUUAGUGGAUCAGCAAGGAGACCAGCUGAAAUGAACAAAGGGAAGAAUAAAUAGGACAUGAAUUAGGUAAAAAAGGAGAGAGCGAUAGUGAUGGCAGGAGGUAUAUUGGGUACAACCUUGUAAAGCAUUGUACAGACUUUUACUAUGAAUAAGAUGGGAAGCCACUGGAGCAUUCUGAGCAAAGUAAUGAUAUGAUAUGACUCAUAUUAAAACAGAACUUCCCUGAUAUAUGGGAAUUGAGUGUCGAGUAUAAGAAUGGAUGCAGGAGACAUGUUAGGAGGCUAAGGCAAUAAUCAAGGUGGGAAACAAUGGUGAAUUUGACCAGGGUGAUAAUGAUGGGGAUGGUGAGAAGUGAUUAGAUUUUGAAGGUUAAAACAACAGGAUUUGCUGACAGAUCGGUUGUGUGGUAUGAUGAAAAAAAAAAGGAAUUAAGGAUGACUGUAAGCUUUUUUUUUUUUCUAGGCAACUUGAAGGAUAGAGUUGGGAUUAACUGAGAUGGGGAAGGCUGUGUGUUAAGCAGGUUUAGGGAGGAGGUGGUGGGAGGAGGGAGCUAAAGAAUUCACUUUGGACAUAUUUAUUUUCAGAUGCCAAUUAGACAUUUCAAGUGAUGAUGCCAUGUAGGCAGUUUUUAGGUUGAAUUUAGGUUUUACAGAAGUCCCAGGCAGGAGAUAUACAUUUUGGCAUCAUAGAAUAUAUAUGGUCUUUAAUACCAUGAGAUGGAUGAGAUCAUCAAUAGAAUGAGUACAAUAGAAUGAGUACAGAGAGAGUUAAAAAGAUGUCCAAGGACUGAGCACUGGAACUCUAACAACACUUAGUGUUAGGGAAGAUAGGGAAGAUAUAAAAUAAUAGCAAAUGAAUAUGAGAAGUAGCAGCUACUGAAGUGAUCCCAUGGAAACCAAAUGAAGAAAGCAAUUCAAAGAGGAAGAAGUCAUCAACUCUGUCAAAUGCUUAGUUUUUUGUUUGUUGUUUGUUUAUUUGGCAAAUGUUUUUCCCUUUGCCUGAAAUGUGUGUAUUCUGCCUCCCCACUUUUAUUUGUAUAUUUUAUUUAUUUUUACUUCAUUUUCAUGUCUCCCCUCCAAUAACUUGUACUUCCAAGAACACUGUGCACACCCAUGUUAUAGCAUUUACCCCACUCCACUAUAGUUCUGUACUCUUAUCUGUUUCUCCCAGCUGGACAAUGAGCAACUCUGAGGGCAGGAGACUCUACAACUCUGAACACUGUACUUGGCACCACACACACACACACACAUUCAUACAUGUAUAACACACAGGCACACAGAUACAUAUGUUUGAAAGUUAAGUAAUUCACCAGCAUCAUUAUCCAGAUAUCUAAUUGGCAGCUAAAGACAGCUAGAAUCUCCAGGGUUCCUUUCUAGUAGCCAGGGUAGUAAAUAUCAAAUCCGAUCUAUGUAUGUUUUCUUACCAGAUUCCUUUUUGAAACUACUUCACUGGAGAUCCUGGGCUUUCUACAAAAUCCUUGUAUUUGACUACAAGACUUUUUAUAUCUCUUUAUAAUUUUUGUCCCUUUAUGGCUAUUUUGUUAUCCUUAUUCUUUGCUUUGAUUGCUUCUACCAUUUCUCCUUCAGAUUUUACAAAGGGAAGCUGUACCUGUCAAUAUUCUGUCUCUGUGAUUGUGCCACACACUUGUUACCUUAUAUCUGGUUAAAGGGUAUAUCCACAGAGCUAAUAUGAUAAAAAUAGUGGAACACAUUCCAGGAUUUCCUACUGAGUGCAAUCCUACCUUAAAUGGAGAGAAAUGAGUCCUUUUUAAGGAUCAGAUGUUUAAUUUAAAAAAUUCAGUGCCUGUUUGUCUUUCAAUUAAAUACAAGGAACCAAGAAAAUCUGCCUUUGAUCAUAUCUUCUUAAUCAAGGGUGUCCAAUCUUUUGGCUUCCCUGGGUCACACUAGAAGAAAAAUUAUCUUGGGCCACACAUAAAAUACACUAACAAUAGCUGAUGAGCUAAAAAAAUUGCAAAAAAAAAAAAAUGUUUUAAGAAAGUUUAUGAAUUUGUGUUGGGCUGCAUUCAAAGCCAUUCUGGCCCACAUGCAGCCCAUGGACAAGCUUGUCUUAAUUAAUGACCUGGAAGUCACUGGACAGUGAUCAUGCACUAUCUUCUCUUUCCAAAAAUGUUUUCUUUGAAUAAGUGAAUACUUUGUAAUACUUCUAUUUCCUAUUUAAAUCCUAAUGACAUUUUCUUGAGUAAAAACUUUGUUGAAAGCAGUACUCUGAUAAAAGUGUAAGAUAAUGAGGCAAGGCAAAAGAGUGUGAGUAGAAUUACGGUGCAAAGAAUUGUUAAUAGUUGGGGAAGGAGACUACCCCAUAGAGCUGAACCACUGUUUGAGCUUCUUCCAUAGCCGGUAAACUCACAGUAGGUAGGGUCCACCCAUAUAAACCGUGGCAAUCUUAUGACAUUUCUCCAAUUUGCAGUCAUAUAUAGAAUAAUUGACAUAGCUCCUUCUCAUAUAUAUCUUUUCUAGACCACACAAAGUGCCGUCUUUUACUUGCCCAAUAUCAACUGUAUCCCUUCCAAAGUAAUAGUUCCCCAACACCUGGGACCAUUAACUGAUUUUUUAAUUAUAGCAUUAUGUUGUUUUACCUUGGAAAUUGUUUAUAUGUUUUCACAGUGCACUCUCACACAAAUUAUUUGACGAAGGGCAUCUUUUGUAUAUUAAACCUUCCAUGCCACAGGGACUGAAAUGAUCUCCUUGUAUAUUAAUUUUUAUGGCAGCUCAGAGAGGCAUUCCUUGCUGUCUGGCCAAAAAUAUAUCAACAUCGUUUAUUGUGACUGUUGCAUAUUUUAUGAUAGGAGUAGACACUGUAGACCACAAAGUGUCCUAUCUGAUACACAGGGAUCCUCAGGGCACCACCUCGCACUUUCUUUUUGUUUUUUGAGGUAUACUCCCAUGUAUACCUAAAUCCAUGCAUACUUAAGUCCUGUAGUUGGCCCUGCAGAACCUGUGUAUACGAAAAGUUGGUUUUCCAUAUAUGUGGGUUUCACAUUCUGUGAAUACUGUAUUUUCUGCAUCUGCGUUUGCAGAGGGCCGACUGUAUUUAUUGAAAAAAUCGCACAUGAGUGGGCCUGUACAGUUCAAAUCCACGUUAUUCAAGCGUCAACUGUAUUUCCUCUUUUGUUAAGCCAAUUUCAUGGCGACAAUUGAAUCCUAUCUUAUCUGGUGUUCGAACAUAUGUGGUAAAAUGCCUUAUGGGCUCGAUUUCAUAAGUUUGCUUGGUUAUCUGUAUCUGUGCAUCCCUCCAUAGUUUUCCAAAGGGGUGCUGAGAACUCCCAGAGACUCGGGGCUGGGGGCUCCAUAUAACCGUGAUAGUAGCAGUCAUCUUGGACAAAGGGCUUUUCCUCGUGGGGAGCGUACUGCUCCGUGCAGGUGAACACUAGGAGGUGCCUGGAAAGGAAGAGCCUUUUAGGCCUUAAACCAAUGAUGUGGGUAUGGCGCCGGCAGGUGCAGGCCAUUAAGACAGCCCUCAGACUUGUUGAAGGCCCCACUUCGCCUGGGAAAAUUCUGGGGAAUCACCACUUGGGCGGGGCAGAGCGCCAGUAGGGCCUGGUUUGUGCGCCGCUGGCAGGGACCAGGAGCGUCUCCCGAACAGCAGGAGAGCGUCCUGCUGCAGCCUUCCGGCUGCACAUGUUUCAGGCAGCUGCCUUCUGGAAAGACUUGGUUGGUGACUGCUAGGAAAGUGGGCGUUGGAGACUAGAGUCGGAAAAUGCUCUUCGGAGGAGGGAGCCCUGCCUCGUGGGUUUGUUGGCCGCCACCGCAUCCGGGGAGUGGUUUCUCGUCCUUGGUCCGUUAAAAGGAACUGUUGCAGGUAAGGCUGGGAUUCUAGGGAGAGGAAGCUGGCAGGAGAGAGGUUUAACGGAGAAAGUAGAUGGUGAAAACAAGAGGGAAUUGAACCAGAAACUAAGUGGUUUGAAAGGGAGAAGUAAGAGGGUGCAGAGGGACGAGUAGAGACAGCAGAAAAAGUUGCACUGAGGUGAUGGAAAUUAAAGUAAAUUCAGAAGAGAGAAACGUAGGGAAUCUUGGCCACACUGUAAGAGGCUAUGGAAAAUUAUAGCCAAGGCUGGUUCACGCCUUAAUGUCUGUCGUGAAAAAAAGAAGUUUUUAUUUUCAGCACUGCAGCUCUGAUGGUCCAGCUCCACCAGGACACAGAUCCCCAGAUCCCUAAAGGUCAGCCAUGCACCCUGAACAGCUCAGAGGGAGGAGCCAGACCAGCAGUGCCUCACACCUUGUUCUCUUCUGCUCUAGACAGAUGGCUCCAUAAUGACAGCUUCAUAAUGGCAGUGGGUGAGCCCCUGGUGCACAUCAGGGUCACUCUUCUGCUGCUCUGGUUUGGGAUGUUUUUGUCUAUUUCUGGCCACUCUCAGGCCAGGCCCUCCCAGUAUUUCACUUCUCCAGAAGUGGUGAUCCCUUUGAAGGUGAUCAGCAGGGGCAGAGGUGCAAAGGCUCCUGGAUGGCUCUCCUAUAGCCUGCGGUUUGGGGGACAGAGAUACAUUGUCCACAUGAGGGUAAAUAAGCUGUUGUUUGCUGCACACCUUCCUGUGUUCACCUACACAGAGCAGCAUGCCCUGCUCCAGGAUCAGCCCUUCAUCCAGGAUGACUGCUACUACCAUGGUUAUGUGGAGGGGGUCCCUGAGUCCUUGGUUGCCCUUAGUACCUGUUCUGGGGGCUUUCUUGGAAUGCUACAGAUAAAUGACCUUGUUUAUGAAAUCAAGCCAAUUAGUGUUUCUGCCACAUUUGAACACCUAGUAUAUAAGAUAGACAGUGAUGAUACACAGUUUCCACCUAUGAGAUGUGGGUUAACAGAAGAGAAAAUAGCACACCAGAUGGAGUUGCAAUUGUCAUAUAAUUUCACUCUGAAGCAAAGUUCUUUUGUGGGCUGGUGGACCCAUCAGCGGUUUGUUGAGCUGGUAGUGGUCGUGGAUAAUAUUAGAUAUCUUUUCUCUCAAAGUAAUGCAACAACAGUGCAGCAUGAAGUAUUUAACGUUGUCAAUAUAGUGGAUUCCUUCUAUCAUCCUUUGGAGGUUGAUGUAAUUUUGACUGGAAUUGAUAUAUGGACUGCAUCAAAUCCACUUCCUACCAGUGGAGACCUAGAUAAUGUUUUAGAGGACUUUUCUAUUUGGAAGAAUUAUAACCUUAAUAAUCGACUACAACAUGAUGUUGCACAUCUUUUCAUAAAAGACACACAAGGCAUGAAGCUUGGUGUUGCCUAUGUUAAAGGAAUAUGCCAGAAUCCUUUUAAUACUGGAGUUGAUGUUUUUGAAGACAACAGGUUGGUCGUUUUUGCAAUUACUUUGGGCCACGAGCUUGGUCAUAAUUUGGGUAUGCAACAUGACACCCAGUGGUGUGUGUGCGAGCUACAGUGGUGCAUAAUGCAUGCCUAUAGAAAGGUGACAACUAAAUUUAGCAACUGCAGUUAUGCCCAAUAUUGGGACAGUACUAUCAGUAGUGGAUUAUGUAUUCAACCGCCUCCAUAUCCAGGGAAUAUAUUUAGACUGAAGUACUGUGGGAAUCUAGUGGUUGAAGAAGGGGAGGAAUGUGACUGUGGAACCAUACGGCAGUGUGCAAAAGAUCCCUGUUGUCUGUUAAACUGUACUCUACAUCCUGGGGCUGCUUGUGCUUUUGGAAUAUGUUGCAAAGACUGCAAAUUUCUGCCAUCAGGAACUUUAUGUAGACAACAAGUUGGUGAAUGUGACCUUCCAGAGUGGUGCAAUGGGACAUCCCAUCAAUGCCCAGAUGAUGUGUAUGUGCAGGACGGGAUCUCCUGUAAUGUGAAUGCCUUCUGCUAUGAAAAGACGUGUAAUAACCAUGAUAUACAAUGUAAAGAGAUUUUUGGCCAAGAUGCAAGGAGUGCAUCUCAGAGUUGCUACCAAGAAAUCAACACCCAAGGAAACCGUUUCGGUCACUGUGGUAUUGUAGGCACAACAUAUGUAAAAUGUUGGACCCCUGAUAUCAUGUGUGGGAGGGUUCAGUGUGAAAAUGUGGGAGUAAUUCCCAAUCUGAUAGAGCAUUCUACAGUGCAGCAGUUUCACCUCAAUGACACCACUUGCUGGGGCACUGAUUAUCAUUUAGGGAUGGCUAUACCUGAUAUUGGUGAGGUGAAAGAUGGCACAGUAUGUGGUCCAGAAAAGAUCUGCAUCCGUAAGAAGUGUGCCAGUAUGGUUCAUCUGUCACAAGCCUGUCAGCCUAAGACCUGCAACAUGAGGGGAAUCUGCAACAACAAACAACACUGUCACUGCAACCAUGAAUGGGCACCCCCAUACUGCAAGGACAAAGGCUAUGGAGGUAGUGCUGAUAGUGGCCCACCUCCUAAGAACAACAUGGAAGGAUUAAAUGUGAUGGGAAAGUUGCGUUACCUGUCACUAUUGUGCCUUCUUCCUUUGGUUGCUUUUUUAUUAUUUUGCUUACAUGUGCUUUUUAAGAAACGCACAAAAAGUAAAGAAGAUGAAGAAGGAUAAGAGAAAUGGGAAAAAGAAGGAGACUAAACUUUAUACUUCAUUUUUAAUAUCCAAUUUUUUAAUAGAAAAAUAUGAAGCCAUGUCUCACUGUUUAAAUAAAACUUCAUGGACAUUUCAUGUCAGGAUUGCAAGCAUUAGCUAUCACAGCAAAGGAUUCCUAGCCUAUUCUUACUUACUCUACAGUGUCUUAAGCAAUAUUAAAGGUUCCUUUUCCCAGAA